AGCAAGUGCGCGUGCGCUGCCUCUCAGCCCAAAUUGGAAACAUGGCCGUACGGUCGCUGUGGGCGGGCCGGCUGCGGGUGCAGCGCCUACUGGCCUGGAGUGCCGCGUGGGAGAGCAAGGGAUGGCCGCUUCCAUUCAGCACUGCCACCCAGAGAACUGCUGGUGAGGACUGCCGUUCUGAGGACCCUCCUGAUGAGCUUGGGCCCCCUCUUGCUGAACGAGCCUUAAGGGUAAAAGCUGUUAAACUGGAGAAAGAAGUCCAAGAUUUAACAGUGAGAUACCAGAGAGCUAUAGCUGAUUGUGAAAACAUAAGGAGGCGAACCCAGAGAUGUGUGGAAGACGCCAAGAUAUUUGGAAUCCAGAGUUUCUGUAAGGACUUGGUGGAGGUGGCUGACAUUUUGGAGAAGACUACAGAGUGCAUUUCUGAAGAAUCGGAGCCUGAGGACCAAAAGCUCACUCUGGAGAAGGUCUUCCGAGGGUUGUUGCUUUUAGAAGCAAAGCUGAAAAGUGUGUUUGCCAAGCAUGGCCUGGAGAAACUGACACCCAUUGGUGACAAAUAUGACCCCCAUGAGCAUGAACUCAUCUGUCAUGUGCCAGCUGGUGUUGGGGUGCAGCCUGGCACCGUGGCAUUAGUAAGACAAGAUGGCUACAAACUUCAUGGCCGCACCAUUAGGCUUGCCCGAGUGGAAGUGGCAGUGGAGUCUCAGAGAAGACUGUGAAGAGGCCAUCAGGAACUGGAUGUUCUCCCAGAGCGCAGUCACCUAUGUUUCUUUUAUUUAUUAAACUAGGUUUGUAUUGUACAUGAGGUACUUCAUGUGAUAUGUUUUGGAUUUAGUCAUAUUGGCUUUAUUUCUAAGAUAUUCUAUUGAUUUAAUGUGACCUGUUUGGUCUCAUCAGAAGUCUUACCAUUGGGCAUUUGAACAGUGUGACAGGUGUUCCAAUGGCCUUUAUCAAAACAUGUUUAGGAAAAUUGGUACUGUGAUAAAUUUGAAUCCAAAAUCCUUUUAACUAUGGGUUUUCAACUACAUGUUUCUUCCUAGCGGUCUCUAUAACAGGAAUUGUGUAGUAUCUUGUAUUUUGUGGAAAAAGGAGAUGGUAGGGAUUGGUUCAACAUUUGGGUACUUAGAGGAUAAAGCUUCGUGGUCGUAUAAAUUUAGAUCAUUUGGAUUGAUUUUUAUACACAUAGAUUUUCAGGACUUUACCUUUUGUUUUGUUUUUUUCCUUUUAGCCAUCUUUUGUUCUUGUAAUCCCAACUAGAUAGGCUUUAUGCUCACAUCAUUGUCCCAUACCCACCCCUUUCUCAUCCCCAUUUGCAGGGGCUAAAGGUCUAGAUGAGACUUGGAAGGCAAGGAGCAUCGAAAUUUGAGAUACCCAGGACCCUUUCAAGCAAGAAUGGCCAAAAAGCCUUGUGCUGUCUUUGCUCUUCAAAUUAUUUUCAGCCUCCUUGUCAUAUAAUCAUUUCAGGCAAACUGAGGCAACACUAACAGCUAAUGACCCAGAUGGCUCUAUUUGGGUAAUUUACCUACAACUUAUUCCACCAGCCUUUACUCCUCUGCCCUUUUGUCAAUUUUACCUUAUAAUCCUUUAUUAAAUGAUGGGAGGUGGUGAUCAGGACAAAAGUGUUAGGUUCCCAUGAUUUCUCAUUUCAUUUAUUAAUAGUUAAUGCUGAAUUUUUUUUUAAGUUUCCUCUGGCUCUAUUUAUGUUACUUUUUGCGAUAAGAACACUUAACAUAAGUAUUCUCUCCUCUUGGCAAUUUUUUUUUUUUUUCCUGUGUUGCCCAGGCUGACCUCCAACUCCUGGGCCCAAGCAAUCCUGCCUCAGCCUGCCAAGUAGCUAGGACUACAGGCGUUCACCACUGCGCCCGCAAAGUUUUUUUGUUGUUUUUUUUUUUAAGUUGGUACUCACAAAUCACUACCUCUGUUAUAUUGACAAGCUCUAUUUCCUAUUCUUUGUAUCUGUUAAGUCACAUCUGUGUAAACAUUGAGCUCACCUUUUAUAUAUUAACCUCUAGAAUUAAUGGGCCUAUGUGGUUUUUUUUCAGUCUUAUAGCUGGUGUUCUGUAAAAGAUUUGUCCAAUAAACGACUUAAUGAAUGAUACAUCAGUCAGAUUUUAGGAAGGCAGUCAAUUAUGGAUAUUUUAAUGUUGGAAGAGGCCUUAAUGAUCAAAUCUCACCCUUUCUGCUUCUGAAGUAUGAAAAUCUAGUCUUUUUAGGACUGGACACAAGGAAAAUAAUCUCUAAACUAUUGACUAAAUUCCAGUGAGAGUAUGAAUGAAGAACAACUAGAUAUUAAUGUCAAUCAUUUAAGAUUAAUGGGCAUGCAAUUAAGUCUCCAUUUAAGAUUAAUGGGCAUGCAAUGAAGUCUCCAGCAGACAAUCAGAUGUUGUUGGAUGUCUAGAUUAUAUAGGUUUAGGUUGAAGUUAUAAAAUAAAAUAAAAUUCAUUUUCCACUGGAACUCUAUGACAUUCAGUGGAGUGGUGGAAAGUUAACCUCUUAUACAUUAUAGAUAAUUCUAAGACAGCACACAAACUUAUCAAUAAAGCCAUCUCCUUGUGGGCCUUACCAUCUUCAUCAGAUUUAGACCCUUAAAAAACAAGUAAAUAUGCACUUUUAAAAUGCAAUCAAAAGACUGGUGGUUAAGCUUGUAAAACCAGAACAUCUUUUGGCAUUCCACUAAGUAUAUAUUGUAAAUUUAAUGAACAAUCAAGGUUCACAAUAGGAAGUUGUCUUUUUUUGCCUUCCAUUCUGUGAGAUUUGACAGAUGGUGACAAUAAGAAAAUGAGCUGAUUGUAAUUACUCUCUGUGUGUUUUUUUAUUGCUAGCUAUCAUUACCAGUUAGAAUUAACAUUAAUUACAAUUAACAAUAAUUUUAGGUAUGGAAUGUUAUGAUUACCUAAAGAGAUGUCUCUACCUAAUGAGCUCAAGUGAUCCUCCCACCUCAGCCUACCAAGUAGCCAGGACCACAGGCAAGUGCACCACCAUGACUGGCUAGUUUUGUUUUUUGGUUUUUGGUUUUUGGUUUUUGGUUUUUUUUUUUUGGUUGGUUGGUUGUUUUUUACAGGCGGGGUCUCACUAUAUUGUCCAGGCUAGAAGAAUUUUCUAAUGGUCUAUUACACCUCCCGUUUUGGCAAGUAAAUUCAGAAUAAUUUUAGGUUCUUUUGUUAUUCAGUAGUUUUGCAGACUUAAAAGUGUAAAUUUAGAAUUAGAAGAUGAAGCUAUAGUAGUAAGAAUCUCAAGCUGAAGGGCUUUGGGGAGCCAAAGCAGCAUAUUAGAGCAUAGGCUUGAACUUAAAUCUCAGCUCAGUCACCUGCAGGACUUUAGGCACCAGUGAUUUCACCCUUCUGAGCCUGUUUCUUUAUUCGUAAAAUGAUUAUAAUAAUUCUUUCACAGCGUUGUGAGGAUUAAGUGAAAUGUGUUAAAUGCCUACUACAGUAGGUGCUCAGAUAUUUAUUUUUAUUUUUUUAUUAUGCACAUUGUUUUUCCUGCCUUUUUAUGGCUGUCUAAAGUCUAGGGAAAAGGGAAGACUGGUUAAUGAUGAGUAGAAAAAACUUGUAAGCUAAUCAUUCACUGACUUAUUUUCCUUCCAUUUUCUGGUUUUUAAAAUUAGCCACACCACAGGAAACCCACAUUUUUAGAUGGAAAGAGCAAGAAAAUUGUGUCAGUGCUCUUAGUUAUUUUCAUCUUAAUGGUAUAGUGAAAAGACAUUGACUUGAGAUGAUACUAAGGAAGCUUUGGCUCACUCUCACUUGAAGAGGGGAUCUUGGUGUUGUAGUACUUGGACUGUACAAAUGUUUUACUGACUUUUCUUACUGCUGUAAAGGAAUCAGGCAGUUGGGUAUUGAUAUGUUAUUUGGUGCUCUCAUUCAUGGCAAAGGAUUUGAUAAAUAAAAGUUCUUUAAACACUAAAGCAAAAUCAAAUGAGCAAAACUAAGGAUGAAAUGUAAUAUUCAUCAGAACAAGGAUCACUGAGAAAAAAUAUUCAGAAACAACUUUAAUAAAACCUGAAUUGAAAUAACUGCA